CCUGUAAGCAAAGAGUAAACAGAUUAAGAAAACAACCAGACGGCUUAACACACCAUCAGUGACUUCCCCCGCCCCUUCCAUUCCCUCUUCAUGAUAUAAAAGACUAGAUAGGCAUGUACUAUAAGCACUGAAAUCUACCUUGUCUUGCUGCUGCCCAAGGCUGCCUUAUAAAUUUCCCCUGGAUAAAUCUUUGACUACCUGCCAACCCGGAAUCAUCUGCCUUUUUUUUUUGGUCUGAUGGCAAAUCAGUAAUUUGCCUCCACUUGUAGAGGGCAAUUCUCAGUCCUGGCAGGGAGUUUUCCCAACAAAAGCAAAGUUACAAUAACACUAGCUUUUGGCCUAAUCAUUGGUUUUUGUUAAUGUAUUGGUCUCAAGUCAUGUUGUAAACAAAAAGUGGAGUUACAUACCAUUGUUACAAUAAUACUAGCUUUUAUAAUUUCCCAUGUAUUUACCUUUACUUAUCUUUAUUUCUUUAUACAAGUUCAGUUACUGUCUAGUGUCCUUUCAACUUGCAGGACUUCAUUUAGCAUUUCUUGUAGGGCAGGUCUAGUGGUAAUGAACUCCCUCAACUUUUGUUUAUCUGGAAAGUCUUAUCUUCUACUUCAAUUUCGAAGGACAGUUUUUGCCAGGUAUGGGAUUCUUUUAUUUUUUUUUUGACACAGAGUUUCGUACUGUUGCCCAGGCUGGGGGGCAGUGGCGCAAUCUUAGCUCACUGCAAGCUCCGCCUCCUGGAUUCAUGCCAUUCUCCUGGAGUAGCUGGGACUACAGGCACCCACUACCACGCACAGCUAAUUUUUUGUAUUUUUAGUAGAGAUGGGGUUUCACUGUGUUAACCAUGAUGGUUUGGAUCUCCUGACCUCGUGAUCCGCCCGCCUCGGCCUCCCAAAGUGCUGGGAUUACAGGCGUGAGCCACUGUGCCUGGCCAGAUAUGGAAUUCUUGAUUGAUAGACUAAAUUUUUUCUUUUACCACUUUGACUAUAUUAGCUCAUUGUCUUCUGGCUUCCAAAGUUUUUGAUAAGAAAUCUGCUGAUAAUCUUAUUGAGGAUCAUUUGUAUGCGAAGAGUCAUUUCUCUUUUGCUGCUUUCAAAAUUCUCUUCUGAUAGUUUGAUUAUAAUGUAUCUCAGUAUGUGUUUCUUUGAGUUCAUCCUACUUGGUUUAUUGAACUUCUUAGAUAUUCAUAUUCAUGUUUUUCAUCAAAUAUGGGAAGCUGUUGGUCAUCAUUUCUUCAAAUAUUCUCACCAGCCUUUUCUCUCUCUUCUCCUUCUGUAGUUAUCACAAUGUGUAUGCUGAUCUGGUUGAGGUAUCGCACAGGUUCCUUAGACUGCUUUCACAUUUCUUCAAUCUCUUUUCUUUCUGUUCCUCAGACUCAAUAAUUUCCAUUAUCCUCUCUUCAAGUUUUCUGACUCUUUCUUCUAACUGUUCAAUGUGCCUUUGAAUCCCUCUUGUGAAUUUUUAAUUUCAGUUAUUGUACUUUUUAGCUCCAGAAUUUCUUUUUGGUUUCUUUUAGGUUUUCUAUCUGUUUUUGAUAUUUCCAUUUUGUUCAUAAAUAAUUUUCUUGACUUUAAAUUCCUUUUGUUUUUUGAGUCUCUUUAGGUUUCAUUUGAAUGGGUUACACUUUCCUGUUUCUCUGUAUCCUUUGUGAUAUUUUUGUUGAAAACCAGACAUUAGAAUUUACUAAUGUGUUAACUCUGGAAAUCAGAUUCUUCCUCUUCUCCAGGGUUUGCUGUUUUUGUUACUGUUUUUAUUAUUUUUGUUUUUUUGAUUGUUGUAAGCCCUCUUUGCCUAAGAUGAGUCUGAAGUAUAAAUCUAAGGUCUUCUCAGAGGUCUUUUCUGAGCCUGCACCAUCCCCUAGGCUGUGCCAUGACUUUCUGAUUUCUCUCAUAUAUGCAAUUGUGUUUAUGUCUGGCUCCCAAAAGGGGAAAAUGAGAAAAAUGAAUGGGAGUGGGGAGGGAAACACCAGCUCUUUAAUUCUCCUGGAAGUCACUUCAACCAGAAGGUGAGGGGCUUGCAACAAUGGAAGUGCAACAAUGGCUAAUGACUCUCUGCACCUCUGUGAUCACGAGUGGCAGUUAGGAAUCAGAGCACAGAUCUAACGUUUUGAGGACAAUGUACUUUUUGCCCCCCUAGCUCCUACAAGCUGUGUGCAAACCACUCUAGGAACAUGUGCACAGCUGCGUGCCAUGAGAUUCAGUGGUAGGAGAUGGUUAGCUGCUGCUGUGCCAAGACUGGAAAUUGACCAAUUUUUUUUUUUUUUUGAGACAGAGUCUCGCUCUGUUACCUAGGCUGGAGUGCAGUGAGGUGAUCUUGGCUCACUGCAACCUCCGUCUCCCAGAUUCAAGUGGUUCUCCUGCCUCAGCCUCCAGAGUAGCUGGGACUACAGGCAUUCACCACCACGCCUGGCUAAUUUUAUAUUUUUCGUAGAGACGGAUUUUGCCAUGUUGGCCAUGCUGGUCUUGAACUCCUGACCUCAGGUGACCCAUCCACCUCAACCUCCCAAAGUGCUAGGAUUACAGGCAUGAGCCACUGCACCCCACCUCUCUUUUCCUUUUUUUGGUCUUAAAACAACAUGCAUUUAUUUGGGUCACAAUGCUAUAGAUUGGCUAUUUGGGCUGGGCUCCGCUGGGCAAUUCUUCUGGUCUCUGUUGGACUCAUUCCCGCAUAUUUUCCCCCAGUUGCUAGGUUGGCUAAGUGUCGGCUAUUCUAAGACAGAUGGCUCACUGCUGCUCCACAUAAUCUCAUCUCCCAGUAGGCUAGCCCAGGUUUGUUCUAUAGCAGCUGAGCAGGAUCCCAGAAAAGCAAGUGGAAGCAUGCAAGACUUCUUAAAGGUUACGCUUAAAACAACUACAUGAUCACUUUCACCACAUUCCAUUGGGCAAAACUUCAUAACACGGCUAGCUCAGAUUCCAGGGUUGAGGAAAUAGAUUCCACUCUUUAAUGAGGGGAGUUACAGAGACACAUUGCAAAUGAAUGAAUAUAGGGAGGAACAGAGAACUGGAGACAUUUCUGCAAUCCUCUUCAAAGCAUUAGCAUAUAUAUUUUGCCUUAGGCUUUAUUUUCUAAGGGACUCAGGCUAUGACAGUGUCUAUUACACUAAUUUUUUUUUAAAGAAAUUGACAAAAUUUAACCACAAUGUACUGUCCAAGUCUUCCUCUGGAAGCUGCAAGUUUCAAUAAAUUCUACAGUUCUAAAAUACAGAUGGUUCCUUGAUUUAUGACGGAAUUAUAUCCCAGAUAAAUCCAUCACAAGCUGAAAAUAUCUUAAGUCAAAAACACACUUUUGACAUAUUAUUUUUAACUUACAACGGGUUUAUCUGGGACAUAACCUCACUGUAAGUCGAGAAGCGUACUAAAAUCUAUAACAUUUUUGGACUAUUGUAAAGUUGAAAAAUCAUAAGUGAAACCGUCGUAAAUCAGGGAUUGUCUGUACAUAAGACAGACUCUGCCAGUGUAAUUUUUGUCUAGGUGAGGAGACAGAUUUCUGGUGCUUCCUAUUCUGCCAUUUUCCUAGAAUCCUCUCCUAUUUGUUUCAUUUUCAUUCAUUCUAUAUUGAUUAAUAUUAAACAUCUAAUAUUGUGACUUUAUAUACUACUUUGGCUGAACUCUCAUGUUUCUAUUUUUUUUGUUCUCAUUGUGAUUAAUUUCUAAAUAGUUUAUAAAUCUGCAAUCACGGUUGCGAUUUUCUCCUUGACCCAGAUUUAAGGCAUUUUUCCCUUUAGCUUCCAAUUAGAUGAAUUUCCUUUUAUCUUUUUAUCUAAAAAAUUAUUUUUAGUGCUGUUAACAGAGUGUGUAACUUAAAAUUGAGAUUUUUUGGGUGUAAUUUUAAAAAUCAAUUUUUAUAAAUGUUUCCUGGUCAUUAAAGGCAACUUCUCUAUCUGCAAGUUAUAAAGUUUAAUAUAGCUGUUAAAUCUUGUAUUACUACUUAGGUUCUUUUAAAAAUUGUCUAUUACUUCCCUGCUGAGGUUUCAAAUACAAAGAAUGGUAUAUAAUCAAACAAUUUAAAGGUGAGGAGAAAGAGAAUGUGAUGGUUAAUAGUGAGUGUCAACUUGAUUGUAUUGAAGGAUGCAAAGUAUUGAUCCUGUGUGUGUCUGUGAGGGUGUUGCCAAAGGAGUUUAACAUUUGAGUCAGUGGGCUGGGAAAGGCAGACCCACCCUUAAUCUGGGUGGGCACCAUCUAAUCAGCUGCCAGCAUGAUCAGAAUAUAAAGCAGGCAGAAAAAACGUGAAAAGAUUAGACUGGCUUAGCCUCCCAGCCUAUACCUUUCUCCUAUGCUGGAUGCUUCCUGUCCUCAAACAUCAGACUCCAAGUUCUUCAGGAACUCGGACUGGCUUCCUUUCUUGCAGCUUGCAGAUGGCCUAUUGUGGGACCUUGUGAUGGUGUGAGUUAAAACUACUUAAUAAACUCUCCUUUAUAUAUAAAUAUAUAUAUCUAUUCCAUUAGUUCUUUCCCUCUAGAGAAACCUAAUACAGAUUUUGGUACCAGGAGUGAUUCUACAGGAACAGAAUAUUAAGGAUGGAGUUCUUUUGUUGGUUUUGGGGUUUCUGAAGUUGGCUGCUUAAUAUGAUUAGACCCCAAAAUGCUAAGGACUCUAAUAGUAUGGAGAACACUGAUAGUCGCUGGCAUGAACUUUUUUUUUUUUUGAGACGGAGUCUUGCUCUGUCACCCAGGCUGGAGUGCAGUGGCGCAGUCUUGGCUCACCGCAAGCUCUGCCUCCCGGGUUCACGCCAUUCUCCUGCCUCAGCCUCCCGAGUAGCUGGGACCACAGGCACCCACCACCAUGCCCGGCUAAUUUUUUGUAUUUUUAGCAGAGAUGGGGUUUCACCAUGUUAGCCAGGAUGGUCUCGAUCUCCUGACCUUGUGAUCCGCCUGCCUCGGCCUCCCAAAGUGCUGCGAUUACAGGCUUGAGCCACCGCGCCCGGCCUGGCAUGAACUUUUUAGAGAGUUAUGAAAAAUAAAUGCGUUUGACACUCCUGAUUCACCACUUGUGAGAGGCAAGGAGUUUAGUGACUCUAUACAUAAUACCUUUGACUCUAUGUGGAGAACAAAGGAACAUAAUUAAGUUGGUUGGUUGUUCCUAAGUUCACUGGACAAAGUGAAUCCAAAGGGAUUCUAACUCCUCGCUCCAGAAGCAGAUACUGAGCCUCAAAUCUAAGACUGUCCUAAGUGAGAGUCUUAUCUCCUGUAGAGAAAGAACUGAAAUUGUGGAAAAACAGACACAAGCUCUUAUUAGGCAAGUGGCUGACCUGCAACAAAAGGUGCAUGCACAGCCUUGCCAGGUGUCUACUGUUAAAGUGAGGGCAUUGAUUGGAAAAGAAUGGGACACUGUAAGUUGGAAUGGGGACACUGAGCUUGUAAACGCUGAUGAACUUUUUUUGCCAAAAGAAACAGCUUCCCCAUCCCGGGUAGCAAGUAGCGGCAACAUCCCCUCCCUGACCCACACUGUCAUCAGCCUUUCUACCUUUGUCGGAGGAGAUAAACCCUACACUGCCUGAGGCAACAGUGAUGGCCUCCCCUGAGGCAGCUGCCAGGCAAGAUAACGUUGAUUCUCCUCAGGAGCCACCCCCAAUACCCUUGUUUGCUUCUGGAUCUAUAACAAGACUAAAGUCCCGGCAGGCCCCUAGAGGUGAGGUUCAGAGUGUGACCCAUGAGGAGGUGCACUAUACUCGAAAAUAACUGCUUGAGUUUUAUAAUUUAUAUAAGCAGAAAUCUGGAGAACAGGCAUGGGAAUGGAUAUUAAGGGUGUGGGACAAUGGUGGAAGGAACACAGAGUUGGAUCAGGCUGAAUUUAUUGAUUUGGGCCCACUAAGUGGGGAUUCUGCAUUUAAUGUUGCAGCUCGGGGAGUUAAAAAAGGUUCUAAUAGUUUAUUUGCUUGGUUAGCUGAAAUAUGGAUUAAAAAAUGGCCCACUAUGAGCGAGCUGGAAAUGCCUGAUCUCUCUCAAUUUAAUGUAGAGGAAGGGAUCCAAAGGCUUAAGGAUAUUGGGAUGGUGGAGUGGAUUAGCCACUUUAGACCUACUCAUCCCAGCUGGGAGGGUCCAGGAAAUAGACCCAAAACCCCUUGAAUGAAGGGGAGGCCAGUCCCCUUGAGGAAGGACCCCGCUAUAUUACCGACAAUUUAUGCUGUUAAUCUUUCUCUCAUUCUCCCCCAAGAAGAUCUCUAGCCUUUUACCAGGGUAAAACUGUGCACUGGGGAAAGGGAAAUGAUCUGACAUUUCAGGGACUACUGGACACUGGCUCUGAGCUGACGUUGAUUCUAGGGGACCCAAAAUGUCACUGUGGUCCUCUAGUUAACAUAGGAGCUUAUAAAGUUCAAGUAAUUAAUGAAGUUUUAGCUCAGGUCCAACUGACAGUGUGUCCAGUGGGUCCCUGGACUCAUCCUGUGGUCAUUUUCCCAGUGCCAGAAUGCAUAAUUGGCACAGGCAUACUUAGCAGCUGGCAGAACCCCCACAUUGGCUCCCUGACUGGUAGAGUAAGGGCUAUUAUGGUGGAAAAAGCCAAAUGGAAGCCAUUAGAGCUGCCUCUACCUAGAAAAAUAGUAAAUAAAAAACAGUAUCACAUCCCUGGAGGGGUUGCGGAAAUUAGUGCCACCAUCAAGGACUUGAAAGACACAGGGGUGGUGAUUCCCACCACAUCCCUGUUCAACUCUCCCAUUUGGCCUCUGCAAAAGACAGAUGGAUCUUGGAGAAUGACAGUCAAUUAUGUAAGCUUAACCAAGUGGUGACUCCAAUUGUGGCUGCUGUAUCAGAUGCGGUUUCACUGCUUGAGCAAAUUAACACAUCUCCUGGUACGUGGUAUGUAGCCAUUGACUUGGCAAAUGCCUUUUUCUCCAUUCCUGUCCAUAAGGCCCACCAGAAGCAAUCUGCCUUCAGCUGGCAAGGCCAGCAAUAUACCUUUACUGUACUACCUCUGUGGUAUAUCAACUCUCUGGCUGUGUCAUAAUCUUAUUUGGAGAGAACUUGAUCUCUUUUUGCUUCCACAAGGUAUCACACUGGUCCAUUACAUUGAUGACAUUAUGCUGAUCGGAUCCAGUGAGCAAGAAGUAGCAAAUACACUGGACUUACUGGUGACACAGAAGAUGGAAAAUAAAUCUGACUAAAAUUCAGGGACCUUCUACCUCAGUAAAAUUUCUAGGGGUCCAGUAGUGUGGGUCCUGUCGAGAUGUUCCUUCUAAAGUGAAGGAUAAGUUGCUGCAUUUGGCCCCUCCUAUACCAAGAAAGAGGAACAACGCCUAGUGGGCCCAUUUGGAUUUUGGAGGCAACACAUUCCUCAUUUCGGUGUGUUACUCUGGCCCAUUUACUGAGUGACCCGAAAGGCUGCCAGUUUUGACUGGGGUCCAGGAGAAGGCUCUACAACAUGUCCAGACUGCUGUGCAAGCUGCUCUGCCACUUGGGCCAUAUGACCCAGCAGAUCCAAUGGUGCUUGAGGUGUCAGUGACACCUCAAGGGAUGCUGUUUGGAGCCUUUGGCAGUCCCCCAUAGGUGAAUCACAGUAGAGGCCUCUAGGAUUUUGGAGCAAGGCCCUGACAUCUUCUGCAGAUAACUAUUCUCCUUCUGAGAGACAGCUUUUGGCCUGUUACUGGGCUUUGGCGGAAACGGAACGUUUGACUAUGUGUCAUCAAGUCACCAUUCAACCUGAACUGACUAUCAUUAACUGGGUGCCUUCUGACCCAUCUAGCCGUAAAGUGGGUCAUGCACAGCAGCAUUCCAUCAUCAAAUGGAAGUGGUAUAUACGUGAUCAGGCUCGAGCAGGUCCUGAAGGCACAAAUAAGUUACAUGAGGAAGUGGCUCAAAUGCCCACGGUCUCCACUCCUGCCACCCUGACUUAUCUCCCGAGCCUGCACCGAUGGCCUCAUGGGGAGUUCCCUAUGAUCAGCUGACAGAGGAAGAAAAGACUAGGGCCCGGUUCACGGAUGAUUCUGCACGAUAUGUAGGCACUACCCAAAAGUGGACAGCUGUAGCACUACAGCCCCUUUCUAGGACAUCCCUGAAGGACAGCAGUGAAAGGAAAUCUUCCCAGUGGGCAGAACUUUAAGCAGUACACCUAGUUGUGCACUUUGUAUGGAAGGAGAAAUGGCCAGAUGUGCGAUUAUAUACUUAUUCAUGGGCUGUAGCUAAUGGUUUGGCUGGAUGGUCAGGGACAUGGAAGAAGCAUAAUUGGAAAAUUGGUGACAAAGAAAUCUGGGAAAGAGAUAUGUGGAUGUAUCUCUCUGAGUGGUCAAAAACUGUGAAGAUAUUUGUAUCCCAUGUGAGUGCUCACCAAUGGGUGAUCUCAGCAGAGAAGGAUUUUAAUAAUCAAGUGAAUAGGAUGAGCCCUUCUGUGCAUACUCAGCCUCUUUCCCCAGUUACGCCUGUCAUUGCCCAAUGGGCCCACGAACAAAGUGGCCAUGGUGGCAGGGAUGGAGGUUACAUAUGGGCUCGGGAACAUGGACUUCCACCCACCAAGGCUGACCUGGCUACGGCCACUGCAGAGUGCCCAAUUUGCCAGCAGCAGAGACCAACACUGAGCCCUCGAAAUGGCACCAUUCCUUGGGGUAACCAGCCAGCUACCCGAUGGCAUGUUGAUGAUAUUGGACCUCUUUUAUCAUGUAAAGGGUAGAGGUUUGUCCUCACUGGAAUAAACACUUAUUCCAGAUAUCGGUUUGCCUAUCCUGCAUGCAAUGCUUCUGCCAAGACUACUAUCUGUGGACUCACAGAAUGUCUUAUCCACUGUCAUGGUAUUCCACACAGCAUUGCCUCUGACCAAGGCACUCACUUUAUGGCUAAAGAAGUGUGACAGUGGGCUCAUGCUCAUGGAAUUCACUGGUCUUACCAUGUUCCCCCGUCAUCCUGAAGCAGCUGGAAUGAUAGAACGGAAUGGCCUUUUGAAGUCACAAUUACAACAUCAACCAGGUGACAACACUUUGCAGGCCUGGGGCAAAGUUCUCCAGAAGGCCAUGUAUACCCUGAAUCAGCGUCCAAUAUAUGAUACUAUUUCUCUCAUAGCCAGGAUUCACAGGUCCAGGAAUCAAGGGGUGGAAGUGGCACCACUCAUCAUCACCCUUAGAGAGUCACUAGCAAAAGUUUUGCUUCCUGUUCCCAUGACAUUACGUUCUGCUGGCUUAGAGGUCUUAGUUUCAAAGGGAGGAACACUGCCACCAGGAGACACAACAGCAAUUCCAUUAAACAGGAAGUUAAGAUUGUCACCUGGACACUUGGGGCUCCUCCUACCUUUAAGUCAACAGUCUAAGAAGGGAGUUACAGUGUUGGCUGGGGUGACUGACCCGGACUAUCAAGAUGAAAUCAGUCUACUACUUUUUUUUUUUUUUUUUUUUUUUUUUGAGACAGAGUCUCGCUCUGUCGCCCAGGCUGGAGUGCAGUGGUGGGAUCUCGGCUCACUGCAAGCUCCGCCUCCCGGGUUCACGCCAUUCUCCUGCCUCAGCCUCCCAAGUAGCUGGGACUACAGGCGCCCGCCACUACGCCCGGCUAAUUUUUUGUAUUUUUAGUAGAGACGGGGUUUCACCGUUUUUAGCUGGGAUGGUCUCGAUCUCCUGACCUCGUGAUCUGCCCGCCUCGGCCUCCCAAAGUGCUGGGAUUACAGGUGUGAGCCACCGCGCCCGGCCCAGUCUACUACUUUUAAGUCAACAGUCUAAGAAGGGAGUUACAGUGUUGGCUGGGGUGAUUGACCUGGACCAUCAAGAUGAAAUCAGUCUACUAUUCCACAACUGAGGUAAGGAAGAGUAUGCAUGGAAUACAGAGAUCUAUUAAGGUGUCUCUUAGUAUUACCAUGCCCUGUGGUUGAAGUCAAUGGGAAACUAUAAAAGCCCAGUCCAGAAAGGACUACAAAUGGUCCAGACCCUUCAGAAAUGAAGGUUUGGGUUACGCCACCAGGAAAAAAACCACGACCUGCUGAGGUGCUUGCUGAAGGCAAAGGGAAUACAGAAUGGGUAGUAGAAGGCUAGUCAUCCAUACCAGCUACAACCAAGUGAACAGUUGCAGAAAUGAGGAUUGUAAUUGUCCUGAGUAUUUCCUCCUUUUGUUAAAAACAUGUUUGUGCAUAUAUACACUUGUACUAAGAAAAUAUCUUCAUUUUAUUUCCUUUUUUUUUGAGAUGGAGCCUUGCUCUUGUUGCCCAGUCUGGAGUGCAGUGGCAGGAUCUCGGCUCACUGCAACCUUUGCCUCCUGGGUUCAAGUGAUUCUCCUGCCUCAGCCUCCCGAGUAGCUGGGAUUACAGGCAUGCACCACCAUGCCUGGCUAAUUUCUGUAUUUUUAGUAUGUUGGCCAGGCUGGUCCUGAACUCCUGAUCUCAAGUGAUCCGCCCAGCUGAGCCUCCCAAAGUGCUAGGAUUACAGGCGUGAGCCACAGCGCCCGACCAUAAUAUUAUUUUUGUGAAAAUAUGUGUUCUGAGUUCUAAACAUUCAGCUUACAAAUCCCCUUUUGCAACAUGAGUGUUUGUAGAGUAUGUGUGUGUUUUGAAUGUGUGCAUGUGAGUAUAUGAAUGUGAAUGUGUAAGUGCACGAGUUUAAGUGCACAAGUGUGUGUUAGUGUGUGCAUGGGUAGGAAUGUGAAUCUGGUUGUGAGUGUGUGUGAGUGUGACUGUGUGUGUGGGGAGGGCUGCAUGUGCUGAGAGCUGUCAAGAAUGAGGACUUCCGUUUCUCCUCACCAAUCUCUAGAUCCUGCCUUAUUUUAUCCUCUCCUAAGCCUUAUGCAAACUUAAGAAAAAUCAGGUUGAGACCCUCUAUUACUGUCAAAAGCCAUUACUCAUCUCGGCCUCCCAAAGUGCUGGGAUUACAGGCGUGAGCCACUGCGCCCAGCCUCCUUUUAUCAUGGGACAUUAAGAUUUACUUCAUAUCAGCAUUUAAGUAUUGUUAACUUUAUGUAAUAGCAUUUGGGUUGGGGACUGGUGUGUUUCCAGCUGUACAAAGGAUAGUUGUAUUAGGUGUAAUUAUGACAUUAUUAUUGUCUUUAUUUGAAGAUUAUGAAUGAUCUCAGGAGAUAUGUAUGUGUUUAAGUUGACAAGUGGUGGACUUGUGAUGGUUAAUACAGUCAACUUGAUUGGAUUAAAGGAUGCAAAGUAUCGAUCCUGAAUGUGUCUGUGAGAGUGUUACCAAAGGAGAUUAACAUUUGAGUUAGUGGGCUGGGAAAGGCAGACCCACCCUUAAUCUGGGCGGGCACCAUCUAAUCAGCUGCCAGCACGACCAGAAUAUAAAGCAGGCAGAAAAACAUGAAAAGACUAGACUGGCUUAGCCUCCCAGCCUACAGCUUUCUCCCAUGUUGGAUGCUUCCCGUCCUCAAACAUUGGACUCCAUGUUCUUCAGCUUUGAAACUCGACUGCCUUCCUUUCUCCUCAGCUUGCAUAUGGCCUAUUCUGGGACCUUGUGAUCAUGUGAGUUAAUACUACUUAAUAAACUCCAUAUAUAUAUAUAUAUAUAUCUCCUAUUAGUUCUAUUCCUCUAGAGAACCUGGACUAAUAAAGAGAACGAGAUAAAAGAGGAAACAACAGAGGCCAUGAUUGCACUUUUUACAUAUAUCAAAUAUUGGCAAGUCUGCCAUCCUAGCUUCCCAUCUGCCUACAAGUGGGCAGAGCCAUUUUUAACCUUUCUUACUGUGAACAUACUUCAAUUCACUUAGAAUUCUUGAAGUCCAGGCCAAGCACCUCUAGGGUAAAAUUUAGCAUUCUGUUUUAUCCAGGUGUUCACUAACGGUUCCAUAUUAAUUUGCUUCUGCAGAUAAAGUAUAAAUUCCUCAUGGGCUAAAAUCACACCUUAUUUUGUAUCUUCCCCUUGCACCAACCACUAGCAUAGUACUGAGUACAUAGUUCAAAUGCCAUUAACUCCACAGUGAUCCUACCUAUGAAGAUAUGACUUGAAGAAUUCUGAAACUCAUUAAGCUAACCUAUACAAGGAUACUAAUUUACUAUUUAUAUACUGAAAUUAAAGCCCUAGUAUGAUGUCUGGGGUUACCAAACACAGUGAUAUAGUAAUUUGGUGGAGGCCAGCAAGGCCAAUGCCAUACUUCUCAGGGUAACUGGAAUUGUGUCUUCAAAGGAGAAGUAAUUCCCACUAUCAACUGGGAGGUACAGGGUAUCAAACUUGUGAGAAGAGCCCUUCUGUAGGCUCAAGGAGUGCCAGUGGCAUUCAAGGAGGAGGGAGGGAGAGGAUUUUUGUCCCCAAGGGGCAUCUAGCAACAUUUUGAGACAGUUUUGGUUGGUGGUGGGGUGCUACUGGGAUUUACUGGGUAGAAGCCAGGGAUGCUGAUAAAAUAAACAUCCUACAAUGCACAGGAUAACCUUCCACAACAAAGAAUUAUCUGACUUAAAAUGUCAAUAGUGCCAAGGUUGAGAAUCCUUUCUUUCAUAGGCAAUCAAGGGAAUUCUUUGUCCUCUGUGCUCAGACCUGAACUUAAAGAGUAAAAUUAUCUAAGAGCUGUUUCUGAGUAAGACAAGUUACGAAAUGGGCACUGUCAUCAGGAGGUGGCAUAUCUAGUUAAAAAAAAAAUUCAGAAAUUGAGUAGUCUUAUUUUGUAUAUAAGAUUAUCCUUAUGCUAUUCUGUUUUCUACUUUUUUUUUUUUUUUUGAGACACAGUCUUGUUCUUGUCCCCGAGGCUGAAGUGCAAUGGCAUGAUCUUGGCUCACUGCAACCUCUGUCUCCCAGGUUCAAGCGAUUCUCCUGUCUCAGCCUCCUGAAUAGCUGGGAUUAAAGGCACCUGGCACCACGACUGGCUAAUUUUUGUAUUUUUAGUACAGAUGGGGUUUCGCCACGUUGGCCAGGCUGGUCUCAACUCUUGACCUCAUGAUCCACCCUCCUCGGCCUCCCAAAGUGCUGGGAUUACAGGUGUAAGCCACUGCACCCAGCCUGUUUACUUUUAUGUUUUAGAGAUGGGGGUCUCGCUGUGCUACCCAGGCUGGAGUGCAGCAGUGCAACUAUAGCUCACUGCAGACUUGAACUCCUGGGCUCAAGAGAUCCUCCAGCCUCAGCCUCCUGAGUAGCAGGAAGUAGAGGUGUACACAACCACACCCACUUUUUUUUUUUUUUUUUUUUUUUUUUGGAGACAGGAGGUCUCACUCUGUUGCCCAGGUUGGAGUGCAGUUUUGCGAUUUCAGCUCACUGCAACCUCCACCUCCCUGGUUCAAGCGAUUCUCCCACCUCAGCCUCCCGAGUAUCCGGGAUUACAGGCAUGUGCCACCACACCUGGCUGAUUUUUGUAUUUUUUGGUAGAGACGAGGUUUCACCAUGUUGGCCAGGCUGGUCUCAAAUUCCUGGCCUCCAGCAGUGCUCCUGUCUUGGCCUCCCAAAGCGUUGGGAUUAUAGGCAUGAGCCACCACACCCAGGUACUACUGUGUGAUUUUAAUAUCCAAUGUUUUUUCUUCUAUUACAAAAGUAUCUUUACAUACUUAUCUUACCCUAAGCCAUUGAAAUUGUUCCAUUUUAAGUUGUACUGACAAAGGAUCCAAAUUUACAGUUUCUGCUCAGCUGUGUAGCAAAGUAUUAAGGAAAGGGUUACAUGUUCACACUUUGAGGCCAAGUGGUAGUGACUCCAAGGACAAAAUGAACAGUCAAAAAACAGGGCUGUAUAAUCCAUCCAUUCUUUCCAACAGUAGAAUUUCCUCCAAUUAUCAAUUCUGGAGAUUCUGGGGUUAUUCAAUUAAGAAGAGUAGCACAUACUUCAGUCACAUGAGGACACUCUCAAAAUACAAGUUGAAAAUACAAAACUCCUCAUAACAAUGUCAAGUGCCAACAAUGAUUUUUAAAAUUUAAGUAGGGCUGAACUGUGUGUAACUGGUGAAAUGUUCAAGUUAACAAUCCUUACACACGAAAUCUCUCACUUCACUGACUUAAUUCAUUAUUUGCUGAAUAAACAAUAAACUUCCAGUCAGUAGUCAAGAGUUGGCAAUCUAGCUGGUAGGACAUAACAUAUAAUCAUGAAACAGCAAAAACAGUAUUCAAAGAUUAAAUUAGCAAUACCCCAAAAUGUGUGUUAGAGUUAGCAUAAAGAAUUUCUGAUGUAGUUUACCAAGAGCUAAACUAAAAAGUCCAGAAUACAAAAAACAGGGAUGCAAUGAUGUUAGUUUUUUUCACCAUCCUUGAAAUUCUCCCAUUAACCACAGCUCUGAGUUUUCAACUGCUCUUUGUCCUUAAAUCUUCAGAUUCCCUCCUUUGAAUGGGAUAGGUAGAGCAGAUUAGAAGAAAUAUAUUCCGAGGCUCUCUAAUAGUUUCUGGAUGAUUAACCUUCAUGAAAAUAACCUCACAGAUAAGUAAUUAGGAUUUUUCAGCCCAUUUCUAUAAACUAAGUAAACUUUUUUUCUAGUGAACAUAACUUGAUAUAUUAGUGACUGUAGAAAGUCUUUCUACAGCAACAGGAAUUAUAUCAAGGCUUUUGCAAAUUCCUGGCAACUCCGGGCAUGUUUAAGUUCUACUACUCAUCUGUUCUGACUAUAUUUUCAUCUGAUGGAAUAAGCAGUUCAUCUCCUUUCCUAGAACUUUUAGUGCUCUACUGUCCCCCUCACUUUAGUUAAGGUCUGCCAUGUCCUCCUCUCCGACAGUCCUUGACUUUCCCAAUGGCAUAUUCAUCUGCUCAAACAGAUGUCACUGCAAAACAAAACAAACUUUUAACAAAAAGCAAUGUUUGCAUAUUUGGGGCCUUUUGUAUGACAAUAUUGCACGUUUCCUCAGAAAAAUUCACGGAGAUUCUUUAAGGUUGGGGGUUUAAUCUAUUGAUAUUUUCCUUAGGUAGACAAAGACAACCUCUAAGUGCGCUCAGUUAAUCUUUAACCGCUACAUCAUCGUCACCCAGGCACUAAGACAUAACUAGGGCAUAAUGAGUUUUAUUUCCACCAGGGGCGCCUAGUAACUACCAGGUUCAACGCUCCCAGGUGGCCGACAUGUGAUGUGCUCUACUGUUUGGGCUGGGGAUAUUAGCUCAACAAACUCUGGCCACAAGGAUCACGCGGAUAUUCUUGGGGAUGCCUAGCGAAAUGCGCUGUACCUAGGCCUCGAACUCUCGCCUGCUCUCCGGUGGGCGGUCUCGAACUCCAGCCUGCUCUCCGGCAGCCCACAGCAAUGCGCCUGCCAAGACCUUAGGCUGCAAAACUCGCCACGGCCCAGAGCUCGCCUCCAAGUGCGCCCCGCACAGGGCAAGCUUUCGGCGAGGACUCGCGUCCCACCCAUCUAGCCCUGGCCGCUGUCCCAACUCCCGCAGUUCACAGAGGCGGCGGCGGUGAGCGCAGCCGAUGCCACAUCCUCAGCGGCAAGCUGAAGAAACCUGUCUCCUCUCUGGGGCGACCAAACGAUACGUCGAUGCCGGAACCGACCCGACGCCGGAGCCGUCGGCUCCGUCCUUACCGUUGCUCUCCAGUUUGGGGCGGGUCGGGGGAAUGGCUGAGGAGAUGGAGUCGUCGCUCGAGGCAAGCUUUUCGUCCAGCGGGGCAGUGUCAGGGGCCUCAGGGUUUUUGCCUCCUGCCCGCUCCCGCAUCUUCAAGAUAAUCGUGAUCGGCGACUCCAAUGUGGGCAAGACAUGCCUGACCUACCGCUUCUGCGCUGGCCGCUUCCCCGACCGCACCGAGGCCACGAUAGGGGUGGAUUUCCGAGAACGAGCGGUGGAGAUUGAUGGGGAGCGCAUCAAGAUCCAGCUAUGGGACACAGCAGGACAAGAACGAUUCAGAAAGAGCAUGGUUCAGCACUACUACAGAAAUGUACAUGCUGUUGUCUUCGUGUAUGAUAUGACCAACAUGGCUAGUUUUCAUAGCCUACCAUCUUGGAUAGAAGAAUGCAAACAACAUUUGCUAGCCAAUGAUAUACCACGGAUUCUUGUUGGAAAUAAAUGUGACUUGAGAAGUGCCAUACAGGUACCCACAGACUUGGCACAAAAAUUUGCUGACACACACAGUAUGCCUUUGUUUGAAACGUCUGCUAAAAACCCCAAUGAUAAUGACCAUGUGGAAGCUAUAUUUAUGACCUUGGCUCAUAAGCUUAAGAGCCACAAACCAUUAAUGCUUAGUCAGCCCCCUGAUAAUGGAAUUAUCCUGAAGCCUGAACCAAAGCCUGCAAUGACGUGCUGGUGCUAAAUAACAGUCUUUAUUAUAUUAUCUAAUUUUGACUAAAGAAAUACUUUUGAAGUAUGACAGUAUUAAGUCAUAAGAUUUAAUCUCAACUAUAAUGGGUCAUCUUGACACUUUGCUGUUUGUCAUUGUCACGCUUUUGUAUUUUGUAUCUACUUAAGUUUGUCACUGUGACAACACAGGAAAAGUUGGUUUUCAGGUGAGAUUGAAAAUGAAGCAAAGAUAGGAUGAAUCUGAACAUCUCUCCAUCUAGAGCCCAAUGAAGGAAGCUUCAAAUGAGAACAUGAUGGAAUCAGUAACCAUUCAAUCUUUUGUCCUAGGAUUGGAAAAAAAUGUUAAAGGUUUAGGACACACCUAAUAGUAUGUCCUUUGAAUGGGAAGUGUUCUUAAUAGGAUAAAAACUGGUAUUUGCCUCUCCCCAGAGUACUUUUUUUGUUUUUUCAUAGAGACGGGGUCUUGCUAUGUUGUCCAGGCUGGCCUUGAGCUCCUGGGCUCAAGCAAUCCUCCCACCUCAGCCUCCCCAGUACUGGGACUGUAGGUACUCACCACUGCAUCUGGCCUUUCUUUGUUUUAUUAACAUAUUUAGUUUUGUUAUUAUUGGUAUGUUUUAGAGCCAAGACUUUAGUUCCAGUGGGAUAAGAAGGCAUAGAAUGUUUUCUGGUUCCCAGUCCAUAAAGAAUGACUUUUCCAAGAGUUCUAGAUGUUUGAUUUUCUAAUUAAUACUUAUCAGAUCUACAAAAAUCAUUAUUAUUUUAAAAGAGUUAUUUGAGUUUCUUUCUUUCUUUUUUUUUUUUUUUUUUUUUGAGAUGGAGUCUCGCUCUGUCUCCAGGCUGGAGUGCAGUGGCGUCAUCUCGGCUCACUGCAACCUCCGCCUCCCAGGUUCAAGUGAUUCUCCUGCCUCAGCCUCCCGAGUAGCUGGGAUUACAGGCGUGCACUACCACACCCAGCUGAUUUUUGUAUUUUUAGUAUAGAUGGGGUUUCACCAUGUUGGCCAGGAUGGUCUCGAUCUCUUGACCUCAUGAUCCACCCGCCUCAGCUUCCCAAAGUGCUGGGAUUACAGGUGUGAGUCACUGCACCCAGCCGAGUUGCUUUCUUACUAAAUCCUAUUAAAAUAUGCAAAAAUAAGUCAGAUUUUAAGGCAAAUAAAGUGACAUAAGGUGCUUUAUAUUUUAUUUUGGUAUAUUUAAACAGUGAAAAACUAACUGAAAGCACAUGAAGAGUUGUAACUUGGGGGAAAAUAGGUAAACAUAGCUUCUAGCUAACACAGGAGACCUAUUCUUAGCCUUUACUAAUUUCAAGCAGUGUAUCCCAUAUGGUAUCUCUUGCUCUUCCUUCAACUCCAAUAAAUUUAAUGACUAAAUGCCAAGUUAACAAAUCAACUUCCAUUUGGAUUGUAGGUGUGAAGGCACAACUCUAAUUGCUAUUAGUCUACAUGUAUUUCUGUAAUAGUAUUGUGUCAUAUCAAUUUUUAAGAUGUCUAAAUUUUAUGGUCACAAGUUAUCCCUCCUCAGUAUGAAAAAUAAAUUAGAUAUUGAAAAAUGUCUAAACUUCAGUGAUGGAAAGAAUAUUUCAAGAAGUUUUUUAACCUAAAUACUUUUAUUUUGAAUUUAAGUCUUUGCACAUAAAAUAUAGCAAGCUUACAUAUUAAACUAUUUACGUAAAUGGAAUGUAAGCCAUGACUUUAACUGAAGUGUUCACAUUCACUAAUUUUGAUAGAUUGCUGUCCUUAAUAAUUUUGGAGGAAAUUAAGCCAAAUGAUUAUUGUACUACAGUAUUUUCAGAAUAUGGGAAAUCAAUUAAAAAUGUAAUCUAAUCUAGUUUAAGAUUUUUGUUUAAUCAUCAUGGUGGUCCUACCUGGAUAAUUUAACUAUAAAGACAAAGUAAUUCUAUUAAAUGAACUAACUGAAAAUAAUAAUUAUAGGAAGUGAUUAUUCCAUUUUAAGUAUUAGAGCUCAAAUUGGCUUUAUUUGCAUUUAGGGAGAUCAUGUUUUCUUAAUCAUGCUGGAAUUUAAAAAUUGUUUUACUUGUAUCGAAAUUAACCUUGAUUUAUAACUAUUUUUGUAAUAAAACAAUGACAGCUGUAGUAACUAUGAUGGGUGUAACAACAUUUUUUUAAAGAAGGGAAUCUGUUUAUCGCUUUUCAAAAUAUUUUCUAAAGUGGGGGAAGAAAGUUUAUAGACUUUCCAAGCACAUUUAUGGUUUUUUAUUACUAUUAUUAUGGUUUUAAAAAGAGUAACUUUAUUUCUUUUUGUAAGGAAUUAAGUAAUAUCCUUUACAGUUCUGUGAAAGGACUUAUUUUUUAACUGUAAUAUUUAUUAGUUUUAAAAUAUUUGUAUCUCAUUUGUAACAAUUUGUUUUAAUUUUUUAUAUAUAUGUUUUUAUUUUUAAAAAACAUACCAGUUGAAUGGGGUUAAAGCUUUCAAUAUCUUAAAAUAUUUAUAAAACAUUUCACUGUUGCAAAAUCACUUCCAAAAUGAUAGCUAUCUAACAACUAAUUACUAAUUUUUAAAGAACAAAUCACACAUUUAAAAAAUCUGUAGAAUUUAUUUUAACUAUGACCUUUAAUUGAAAAUAAAUAAUUAAAAUAUCAGACAUGUUUUGGAAAAGUCUUAAUUUGAGAACACCAAAGGAAACUACCCCAGAAUCUAAUGUAGUUCGCUAUUAAUAACAAUGCAUUAUUGAAAGUAUAUUGCAAAUACAUGUUUCCUCAUGAAAUCUAAGUAAUUUUGUUGUGGAAUAGUGUCACUGUUACAUUUCCCCCAUGAAGUUCAAUAAACCAGCUUAGCCACAAAGAAAUUGUGUUUUAUUUUCUUUGUUUGGUUACUGGGUAGAGUAUAAAAUAAAACAAUCUUUUUUUCCUCCUGGUUUCCAGAUAAUAUUAUAUAUAUGAUACACUUUUGAAAACAACAAAAAGCCCCCAACCCAUUGGACAAUUAUUUUCUUGUAUACAUUUGAGGUCAAAGAACACUUCAGGAAAAAAACUCAACAAAGUAUUAAAAUUAGCUGAUAACACAGCUUUUGUAUUUGUGUGUUUUAGUAAUCCAGCUUGUUUUAGAAUAGUUCAGUGCAAAAAGCAAAUGGUGCAAGAGGAGUUGAUGUGUAUUUAGACGUAAAAGCAUUUAACAGAAUGAAUAACUAUAGAAAGUAUGAGAAAAGAGAACGAACUACGUCUCAGGUAUAAGAUUGCAGUUACUGAUUUAGACACCAUAGGAUUAGGGAUGUGGGGGCCUCUGAUGUUGAUUCUGCUUCCCCUGGUCAGUUUAUUUUACGUAUAAGUUACCCUUGUGUUCAAACACAAAAUUGACAUUAUUCAUGAAGGACUGCUUUCUUAAUCAGAUAUUAAGAAGUUCGUCAUGUAUUUUGGGAGCACGUUUGCUACAGCCUGUGUGGCAAGGGCGAAUGCACUUGGUUUGUUGGAAUAACCUGAUUUAUCAAACAUUUAUCAAGUAUGGGUCAUGUGUUCUCUAUUUGUGUUAGUGGAGCUACAUA